CUCUUCCGGUCUUUCUGGUCUCGGCCGCAGAAGCGAGAUGACGAAGGGAACGUCAUCGUUUGGAAAGCGUCGCAAUAAGACGCACACGUUGUGCCGCCGCUGUGGCUCUAAGGCCUACCACCUUCAGAAGUCGACCUGUGGCAAAUGUGGCUACCCUGCCAAGCGCAAGAGAAAGUAUAACUGGAGUGCCAAGGCUAAAAGACGAAAUACCACCGGAACUGGUCGAAUGAGGCACCUAAAAAUUGUAUACCGCAGAUUCAGGCAUGGAUUCCGUGAAGGAACAACACCUAAACCCAAGAGGGCAGCUGUUGCAGCAUCCAGUUCAUCUUAAGAAUGUCAACGAUUAGUCAUGCAAUAAAUGUUCUGGUUUUAAAAAAUACAUAUCUGGUUUUGGUAAGGUAUUUUUAAUCAAUUAGGCUUGUAGUAUCAGUGAAAUACUGUAGGUUUAGGGACUGGGCUAGCUUCAUAUCAGAUUUACUUGUUAAGUGACUGUUUUGGAAUGUUUACUUUUGGACUGGGUUUGUAACACGGUUAAAGGCAAUGAGAAACAAGCAGAAUUCCAGGAGUCCUUGAAGCAGAGGGCACUGGAAGACAAUAUAGCAGAUUAAAAUAGCACAGCUCAUGUGGCAUAGGUGGGUAUUUUAGAUGUUUGAGUAAAUUUGAAAGAGUAUGAUGUUUAAAUUACCUUUAGCAACAUGUUCAUCUGCUAUGCUGUCAUGACUAGGGGGAUGAUUAUUAGUCACAUAGAGCUUGGGAGUACCACUGGAAACGUAUGGGUAGGAGUUUAGGUGGCUUCUGUUUUUCAAAAGAUGAUCUUAUCCUAGUAUCUGUAAUGCUCACUUGGCACACCUGACUUGUGGGCUGUGUGUAAGGUGGCUAGCUAAGUGAAAAAAGCCUGCUAGGUGUGAGUCAACUUAAGAAUAUGUAAAUAGGUUUGAGAAAAAGUAGGGCUUGGGUGCAAGUAAAGAUUGAGCAGGAAAUAAAGGAAAAUCAAGUAUAAUCCCUGAGAUUUGUAGACUAAAGGCAAUGAUGUGGGACUACUUGGUCGAAUUUUUUUAGCCCUCAACUUGGUAAUUGGGUGUUUCUGUGUUAAAGCACUGAAACUUGCUGUCGUGCCUUCCUAGUUUUCGUGGUUUAUUGACAGGGUUGGGGGUUUUUUUUGUUUUUUUAAAAUGAAGGGACAAAGUCAACUGGACUGCUGAGUGAGAGGGCAGGGGCAGUUGAAGGGAACAUGAAUUGCUGGAACAGCUACAUAAAAUAGUGAUGUAGCCAAGUCAUGCUAUUUAAAUUAUAAUUCUCCACUGUGUUUAGAAUAACAUCUGAGGUUCUUAACCUGGCCUUGGAAGGGUAUCACUUUUACUUGUAACCUGGAAUGGCUUUAUAAUGUGCUAGCUAAUUGCUACUCUCAUCUUGUAUUUUAACUCCUAAUUUACCCUUCAGGUCUCAGCUUCAGAACAUUCACUUAUAAAGAAACCCUGCUGAUUAAAUCUCUCUUGGGCUUCCUCCCGAAAUGUGAGACUAUACUUUAAAGAUGUAUGGUUAGAGUCCAAUUGCCAUUGCCUUUCUUGUUUACAGAUAGUGCAAUGGCGCAAUCCUGGCUCACUGCAGCCUCUAAUUCCUGGGCUCAAGUCAAGUGGUUCUCCUGCCUCAGCCUUCUGAGUAGCUGGGACUACAGAUGCACACCACCACACCUGGCUAAUUUUUGUGUUUUUUGUAGAGAUGGAGAUUCACUCGACUAAUUCUUUUUGUAUUCUUAGUAGAGACUGGGUUUCAACAUGUUGACCAGGCUGGUCUCGAACUCGACCUCGUGAUCCGCCGCCUCGGCCUCCCAAAGUGCUAGGAUUACAGGCGUGAGCCACCACUCCCGGCUGUCAUCAUCAAAUUUUCAAGUGAAGAUAGUCUGUUGAAGAUUGAACAAUGACCUUGAAAGACAGCUGAGUUGCUGUGGGUAUAAUGUAAAGCUGGUGAAGUUUGGCCAGUUUGGGCUUCAGAAGUCUAAGUCUAGUGAAGGUACCCUGACCCCCAUAUAAACAACCCUUGAGGCCGGUGUGGUGGCUCACGGCUGUAAUCCUGGCACUUUGGGAGGCCGAGGUGGGCGGAUCACAAGGUCAAGAGAUCGAGAUCACCCUGGCCCACAUGGUGAGACCCCAACUCUACUAAAAAUACAAAAAUUAGCUGGGUGUGGUGGCAUGUGCCUGUAGUCUUAGCUACUUGAGAGGCUGAGGCAGGAGAAUCGCUUGAACCUGGGAGGCAGAGGUUGCAGUGAGCUGAGAUCAUGCCACUGUGCUCCAGCCUGGUGGCACAGUGAGACUCCACCUCAAAAAAAAAAAAAAAUCCUUGAACUAAUGACUCAAAUUUUCAAAUGAAACAAAAUAAGCAGUGGAUCUUGCAUUGGAGAUGGAGUUAAACUAUGUUGCCCAGGCUGGUCUUGGACUCCUGGUUUCAAGUGAUCCUCUCAUCUUGGCCUCCCAAAGUGCUGGGAUUACAGGGACGAGCCACCACACCCCACCUAUUGUCUAUAUUUCUAUCUUUAACAGCACUUCAGUCCUGCCUUAAGUUAUAGUUAUGUAUAGAUACCCAUUAUACUUUAAAUUUUUCAGCAGAAAUUAUGCUUUUAUCUUCUCUGCAGUGUUAUAUGUUGGUGUGCAAAAAUGUUAAAUUUAUUUUUCCUAAGUACCCCAUCUGCUUUUCAACUCUGUCCUCUGCCUGAAAAGCCUCCCUCCAGCCCCUACUUCCCUCCCAUCUUAGUUCACAAAGUCAGGUUGAUUUGCCCCCAGCUGUCAAAGCAGACUACCUGUUUCCACAUGUAACUGGUUAUGUUCUGUAAAGUUACAAAAAUAGAAAGGUUGAAUCUGUGGCGGCCGGGUACGGUAGCUCACGUCCUAUAGUCGCAGCACUUUGGGAGGCCAAGGUGGGCAGUUCACGUGAGGUGGGGAGUUCGAGACCAGCCUGACCAACAUGGAGAAACCCCGUCUCUACUAAAAAUACAAAAAUAUUAGCCGGGCGUGGUGGUGCAUGCCUGUAAUCCCAGCUACUAGGGAGGCUGAGGCAGGAGAAUUGCUUGAACCUGGGAGACGGAGGUUGCGGUGAGCUGCAGAGGCCUCACCUCUAAUUGAGACACAAUUAUAUAUUGUUGAUAUAUAUAUAUAUAUAUAUACACACACACACACACACUAUGAUGGAUAAAUGCAUGAGUUUCUGUGAGAGCAUUGGAAAGGAGUUUGUCACUCAAUAGGUGAAGCCAGGCUAAGAUUUAAGCUGAGCCAGGGAGGACUUGAAGGAAUCAUGAUGAGAGAGAAGGUAAGUGGCUUUGCCAGCAAUGAAACAGCUGACAUAAUGGUAACCAGUCAGAGGAGGGCAUAACUAUGAAACUGGACACCUUGGUUGUCAGGUUAGAAGGAUGGGGUGUAGGGUUGGUAAGAAAAGAAUUCAGGGAAGAGCAGCGAUCAGAUUAUGAAGAAUUUGUCUUGAGAAAUUACAGAGGAUUUAAACCAGAAUGUUAGGAAUAGUUAUUCUAGCAAGAUGAAUGUGGAAAGUGUUAGUGUGCAUGUGAUGAGUCUUGAAGCUGGAAACUAGGUAACAGGUUCUUAAAUAGUUCAUGUGAAAAUCAUGACAGACUAAGGCAGUGGCUGUGGGGCUGUCCGGGAGUUCUCUACAGAAAACAUCUAAAACUUGAAUGUGCAAGUGAGUAGCUAACUUCCAAGCUUCCCAUUUCUGUAUAAUUUAAGCAUGAAAAUGAGAACACUGAGAUUUGAUAGGCAUGUAGAAGUCAGAGUAAGCAAGAGGGCUUGAGUUCAUCGAUGAACUUCAGUAACUAUCCUUGACUUAGUAUUGGUGGAAACCAUUUGUGAAUUUACAGACUCCAAAAACAAAAAGAUAAUUUAGAGUCUCAAAGUAAGAUUUGGGGAGAUGUCCAUUGGAGACAGAAGUGGAGAGAGGGAGAAGUUCAUUUGUUGACAUAUUUAUGUAUGGUGCACCUACUGUGUGCCAAGCCAUGUUAGAGAUACAGUGGGAGCAAAACCAGAUGUGUUUUCUGCCCUCUGACUCCAGUGGUUGCAGAAUUAGCCCAGGAACUAGAAUUGGAUGGAGUCACACAAACCAAGGAAGGGGAUUGUUUGAGGGGGGCACUCAGUCACAUGUGGCUGAGGCCAAAGAGAAUGAAGAUAUAUUUUAAAAUUCUGGAUUUGGCAAAAUUUAGGCUAGUCUUUACUUUUCAUAAACCUCUCUCAUGUUAGAGCAGCAAAGAAAAACCAGUUUGCCAAGAGGUCACGAGAUUGGGCAGUGAGGAAUGGGGAGUUUAGUUUAAAAGACAACACUAGAUACUUUUGGAAGUUUACCUAUUCUGUGGUUCCCUUUUAUUGACUAAAUGGUGCCCUUCAUUCAUGAAGCAAGUAUCUAUUUAGUGACUACUAUGUGUCAAAAGCUAUCUAGGCCCAGAAACUUUUAAGUGGAAAACAAAACAAAGACCCUGCCCUGACAGAUUUCAAUCAUGUAUAUACUGUAUGUAUGUUUGUGGAAGGUGACAUAAUAGACAAUUGCAGAUAGUGAUAAGUGUGUAAGACAAGGAUACCACGAGCGUAAUAGACAGUGGGGAUGGAGGAACCUUUAGAAGGUUGGUUAAGUUGAAUGAUAAGGAGCCAUUCUUUUGUCUUUACCUGAAUGACUUAUCAUUCAGCCCUUUUUGAGUUUUGGGUUGCUUGCAGAGUUUAACCUUGCCUGUAAUUGAAACUUAAUUUUGUAAUAGCAUAACUUCAUGUAAGAAAAGCAAAGCAAUACAUUACAGAAUUAUUUUACUGAAGAACUUGUUUCAGAGAAAGAGGCUGUUUCACAUUUAUUAGCACAUUUGGAUUAUAUUUAGGUGUUUUAUUUUUUUUUAAACAAAGGAGUUUGGAUCAUAAUACAAGAGAAGCACAGGGCAAAGACACUGCAUAACCUCAAGAACUAAGAAUGGAAGGACUGGCCAGGCCUGGUGGUGCACACCUGUAAUCCCAGCUACUCAGGAGGCUGAGGCGAGAGAAUCGCUUGAGCCUGGGGGGCAGAGGUUGCAGUGAGCUGAGAGAACGGCGGGCGGCAGAGCGAGACUCCAUCUCAAAAAAAAAAAAGGAUAAAGGAAGGACUUAAGCAAAAUCUUCCUUGUAAGUAGAAGGAUGUUUUGACAAGAAAAGUUGCAAUGGAAAAAUGGUUCUCAUGUACACGAGUAUGUAGAAUAAGCAUCGUGUGUGGAUUGGAUUCAGAUCAAAACAUUGCUUUUAUGUUUGUGUCUUUAUACGGUGGGAGUAUACCCUGGUGCCCCAGGAUGAAGACUUGACCUGACCCAUGUAUUUUUAGAUUACUCACAGAUAACAAAAAGUAUUUUCAUCAUGAUUAGUUGCGAAAACAGUUUUAUUUCAAUAGGUAAAACGUGCAGUCCUAUGUAAUCGUCAGAAGGUAAUCUUAAUUAUAGCUUGGGUGUGCUUUAAACUGCAAGCUGGCAGUGGAGGGCACGAUUCCUCUGAUUUCAGCUUUCUCCUUAUACUUUUCUGGAGCUGUGAGCUGCAAGUUAACUCAGUGGGAUUAAAGUGUAGACUGGAGGUACAAAAGGUGAGGAGUGAGGAGAUAGGGUAGUUCUUCCUUGGCUGGCUGGCUUCAUAAUCCCUGGGCCCCGCAGAUAAUUAAAUCGACUUUUUCUGUCUCAGGCAUUUGUAUGACCUCUUUGGAGGUUCCCUGCUGGGUAGUUAUCCUUGUAUCUGAUGGACCCAUCUCAAUUUAAAAUACUCUGCCAGGUUCGGAGGUUCAUGCUUGUCAUCCCAGCACUUUGGGAGGCUCAGAGGUGCCAUUGGCUUGAGCCCAAGAGUUUGAGACCAGCCUGGGCAACCUGGUGAAACCUCUUCUCCAUUAAAAAUACAAAAAAUUAGCCAGGCAUGGUGGUAUGUGCCUGUAGUCCCAGCUACUCAGGGAGCUGAGGUGGAAGGAUUGCUUGAGCCUGGGAGGUCAAGGCUGCAGUGAACCUUGAUUGUGCCACUGCACUCCAGCCUGGAUGACAAAGACCCUGUCUCAAGAAAAGUCUGUAAUUCUUUCCUAACCCUUAGUAUCCAGCCUCAGUCCUGAGGUUUUCUUUACCUCUGGGGGCUAUUUUAUGCCGGCUCUCUCCUGAGUGUCACACAUCUGGUCCUCAGGAAACAUUCUCACAUCCCUGGCCUGAAAAAAACAAUUUCAGGGAGAUCGCAUGGCAGCAGCCCUCUCUGGGCUCCCCAGCUAAAUGGUUGUACGAAACACAUUUCAAAGCUCUCUGAAGGGCUUCCUUGAAGUUCCUUUCACUGGGUUUCAAAGUAGAAGGUAGUAACUCCUUUGUCCAAGAAGGCUGAAUUGAGCACUUAACAAUUCUCCAAAGAAAUUUCUUCAUUGGUCUCUAUCCUAGACCCCUUCUGUAUCCUUGAUAUGGCUGAGGAUUCUAAAAAAUGACCAGUCUUACAUGGGAGGGCUGGGAUAUAAAAAAUAAAAUAAUAAAUAAUGAUAAAAACUGAAAACUGACCACGUUCUUGGAUAUGUUUUCUUUGGGUUGUGUGUGUGUGUGAGACUUUUGAUAGUUACCCAAAGUAGGAAAAAUCCCAUUCUAAUAAGGUUAUAUUUAUGUAGCUCUGCAAAUAAACAUCUAGCAAAUGUAAAAAGUAUUUUCUUUGCCUUAAAAAUGAUUAAAAUUAUUUGAACUCCUGAGGAGUGUUAUAUGAAUAAAAUUAGUAAGUUAUUUGGAGGAAAGUUAUUUUUUAAAAAGACAACUGGUAAAACAGUACAGGAGAAAGGCCAGCUUCCUCAAGUGAGGACAGUUGUUUAGAAUUGACUGAGGAGCGGCCGGGUGCGGAGGCUCACAUCUGUAAUCCCACACGCCUUGGGAGGCUCUGAGGCGGGUAGAUCACCUGAGGUCAGGAGUUUGAGACCAGCCUGGCCAACAUGGCGAAACCCCGUCUCCACUAAAAAUACAAAAAUUAGCCAGGUGCAGUGGCACACACCUGUAAUCCCAGCUACUCCGAAGGCUGAGGCAGGAGGAUCACCUGAGCCCAGGAAGUUGAGACUGCAGUGAGCUGAGAUUGCACCACUGCACUCCAGCCUCAGUGACAGCGAGACUGUCUCAAAAAAAGAAAAAAGUGACUGAGGAGGAAGAGGCCAGGUGGCAAAUGGAACAGAAUCACCAAAGGGUGAACAGGACUAAGGCAAUGUAGUGUAUGGCUCAGCUACGUCAGAGUGGAAAAGGUGUUAUUAGAGCAGAAACUAUGGUCCCUGCGUCACAGGGAAGCAACCUACAGAGAAGCAGCAGCUCCCCAAGAGAGGAGAGAUAAGAAGCCAGAAGCCUCAGAGUGAACAAUUGUCCUAUUAGGGAUUGCUCUAGAGAGAGAAACCUCUGGGAACGUACCCCUGUGAGGCAGCACAGCACAAUGCUUUUAGAAUUGUAUGAGAGUUGAUAUAUCUCCAUUUGUUUUGCAAAGGCAAAAACUAAGAUACAGAGAUUAUCUGUUAAAGUUAUGUAUUUCUUUGGUAAUAAAGAUGCUGACAGUGUUGCUGGAAUGCAUUUCUUUAAUAAAGAUAUUGUACAAUGAAA